CUCUUGGCUCCGCUAGUGCCCGGCGCGCCGCCGCCAGUGCUGCGGGCUCCGGGCAAUGGAUGCCCCCGGGGCCCUGGCCCAGACCGCCGCCCCCGGUCCGGGCAGGAAGGAGCUGAAGAUCGUGAUCGUGGGCGACGGCGGCUGCGGCAAGACCUCGCUGCUCAUGGUGUACAGCCAGGGCUCCUUCCCCGAGCACUACGCCCCAUCGGUGUUCGAGAAGUACACGGCCAGCGUGACCGUUGGCAGCAAGGAGGUGACCCUGAACCUCUACGACACGGCCGGGCAAGAAGACUAUGACCGGCUGCGGCCCCUGUCCUACCAGAACACCCACCUCGUGCUCAUCUGCUAUGACGUCAUGAAUCCCACCAGCUACGACAACGUCCUCAUCAAGUGGUUCCCUGAGGUCACGCAUUUCUGCCGCGGGAUCCCCAUGGUGCUCAUCGGCUGCAAGACAGACCUGAGGAAGGACAAGGAGCAGCUGCGGAAGCUCCGGGCCGCCCAGCUGGAGCCCAUCACCUACAUGCAGGGCCUGAGCGCCUGCGAACAGAUCCGAGCUGCUCUCUACCUGGAAUGUUCCGCCAAGUUUCGGGAGAAUGUGGAGGACGUCUUCCGGGAGGCCGCCAAGGUGGCUCUCAGCGCUCUGAAGAAGGCGCAACGGCAGAAGAAGCGCCGGCUCUGCCUGCUGCUCUGACCCAGGGCAGACAGACCUCACGACAGCACUGACAGGGCCCGGGGGCCCAGGUGCCGAUUGCACCAGGGAGGCUGCCCCAUCCCGACCCUCCAGCUCAUGGUGUCUGGGGCCUGCGGCUAGACUCUUGGAACAUUCUGGAACUCUCUCCUUUCCUGGCUGGGGCUCUGACCACAAACUCCCCUCCAGGCUGCCCCUGGGACAUGGUGGUGAUGUGGGUGCAGGAGCCAGUGUCUGUUGUCGGGACUCGCAAGUGCCCUCAUCACAGCCACCCCCACCACGAGUGUCUCCCCAGUGCAGACUCAAGUUAUGCUUGAAAUGAAAAAGUCUAUCUGGUAGUGGGUAAACGUAGACCUGGCACUGUUCCACGCGGGCGCCCCAAGCCUGCCACUCCUGUGUCCCUGCCUCCCUGGGCUCCCGAGAUAGGCACCACUGUAUCCUCCAGCUCCUUCCUUCCUUCCCCCAGGAACACGGAGGCCACCGAGGGGGCUGGGCCUAUCAGGAGGACACAGGCUGCAGCCUGGCACCCACCCCUCCCAUCUCCACCCCACAUGGAAGACUUGUCUUCAACUUGGCCACUGUCUUUGCAGAGCUGGGCACAUGUGCCCAGGGGGCAGAAAAAAUGGCUUCUCAGUUGUUAAAAGUAUACCCUGGACCACCCAUCUGACCAUCUCCUUAAGGUUUCACCCAAAGCCCCCAGUGUCAGAGACUUGGGAUGGGAAGAACAGUCGGCUCCCAGUGUGGUCAUGAGCAAGUUUUCUGUGGACUGUUCCCCCCACUGUGGUAGGACAGGACUGGCCCACUUAGUCCUCAAGCUCCCAACCUGCUGUCCCUCAAGCCCCGCUUCUACCAGCCUGUGGAGUUCAGGAGGCGAGACAUCCUGGCCUCCUUUGAGAACUGAUGGGAUCUACCCCCUGUCCACGCGGGACAGUUUCUCAGAACUGGUUCAUAGACCACCUGUGUCACCAACAGCCAGAUACCUAAUCCCUGAGCCUCCUUUGGGAAGGUCUGGGGCCGAGGGUCUGGGAAUUUUUUUUUUUUUUUUUUUUUGGGACAGAGUCUCAUUCUGUCACUCAGGCUAGAGUGCAGUGGCAUGAUCUUGGCUCACUGCAAGCUCCACCUCCUGGGUUCAAGCGAUUCUCUUGCCUCAGCCUCCUGAGUAGCUGGGACUACAUGCGCACACCACCACGUCCGGCUAAUUUUUGUAUUUUUAGUAGAGACAGGGUUUCACCAUGUUGGCCAGGCUGGUCUUGAACUCCUGACCUCGUGAUCCACCCGCCUUAGCCUCCCAAAGUGCUGGGAUUACAGGCGUGAGCCACCGUGCCCGGCCCAGGACUUUUAAAACAAGCAUCCCAGGGGAUUCCGGUGCCUACCAGAAGUCGCAAGCUGCUUGGCUCUGGAGGGCGCCUAGGAGUCGGUGUCGCCUAAGAUGGGAUAAUGGCUUCAGGCAACUCCUAGCCUUCCCCAUAUCUCCUGCCUCAGCCCCCCUGGCCCAGUGCUGGGGCGUCAGCUAAACCUGAGCUUCCAAGAAGUCAGGUUGCCAAAGGAAGGAGCCUUCUGAGACCCUCCCCAACCCACCCAGGUUCCCAAGGCCCUGCCGUACCCUGGGGAAUCAACCAAGGAGUUCUUGUUCUCGAAGAACCCCAGGCCUCAUGAUGGUCUACGGUAGAGGUCCAACAACUACAGCCUGUGGGCCACAUCUGGCCACAGCCUGAUUUGUAAAUAAAGUUUUAUUGGAACACAGCAA